AUUGGGCACCGCCCACUUCGUGGGCUUCCAGGCUGAGUCAUCACUAGAGAGUGGGAAGGGCAGCAGCAGCAGAGAAUCCAAACCCUAAAGCUGAUAUCACAAAGUACCAUUUCUCCAAGUUGGGGGCUCAGAGGGGAGUCAUCAUGAGCGAUGUUACCAUUGUGAAAGAAGGUUGGGUUCAGAAGAGGGUUGUUUGAAUCUGUGGAUGAGAAACUCAUGGGUUCAGAAUGGCCUAUCACAAACUGAGGAUUAUGGAAAAAUACUGUAGUUUACAGAAUUCCCAGCAACCAAAAGUAAGCCUGAGUUUGUACCAAGGUAGGAAGUAUUUUAUGUUUUAUCAUGUCUGCUAGUCUUGUUCUAUUAAAUUACUUAAGCAACUUUUUAUUAUAGGAAAUUUGGAAAUGUGAGAUGUUUAGCGCAAGGAAAUGAUCUUAAAUGGAACAAAGCUGGUUAAGAAAUUGAAAUGAAUAAAAAGCAUGUUAUGAAAAUAUGCAACACUCUCAUUGACCUAAUUAAAAUAGCUUAUAUAAGAUUAUUGUUGGACUAUGUCUUAUAAACUUACAAGGGAAAUCUUGAUUCCCUCUCUUUAACUCCUUAUAGUUAUUGCCAAGAUUAAUAUUCUUACAUGUAUAUUUUUACAAAUAUGUAUGAUAGAAUGGUCACUGUAAAAAAGUUCUAUUUUUAAAAACAUUGGCAUGAGAAAAAGGUGAAUGCUUCUUAAUAAAGUAUUGGAAUAAUUAUUUAUUAGUGUUACUGGAAAUGGGUGAUUCAGUGUCACUUUUUGGGUAAUGUGGAUUUGUUUUGAGAGAGAAACAGAGAAACAAGGAAACAAAAAUCAACAAAGACUAACAAAAUUUCUGCCCAGAAUACAGGUACGUGCUUGCAUGAAACAAAGGUCCUAUCAUGAAAAUACUAAAAGUCUUUGAAGAACUAGGCUGGAGUUUAUACUGUUAGUGUUCUUUAUUGACGAUAUAUGGAACAUACAGUUAUAUAUGUGAUGAAGUUAACAUUAAUGAUAUAAAUUUCCCAGAUGUAGGGCUAACACUUCUUCAAAAAUCAGAUUUCCAGGUAUUUCAUAGCUUGAACAAAUAUUUGAUGAGACCCCUCCCCUGAAAUUUUAUACCCUAGAACUUAAUAAACAUGCCUGGAAAUUUUAUGUAGAUGAAGGAUUGGGGUUUCUAGAGGUCAUGGCAUAAGUCAUUCUUUCCUACCUGGCCUUUGUACAAUACCAGAUACAAAAUGAAGAGUAAAGAUAGAGGCCAGAACGUACCUACUAAUGAUAAAAGUCCAAGUGGAGGUCUGAGUUUGAGAGCCAAAUGACCUGCUGAUUGAAUUGCAGAACCAGGCCAACUUUUUCAAGCACUCUUCAGGUAAUAUAAAUAAGACAGUGCCAUAGAGCAGGGAUCUUUAUGGUUUUUGUUGCAAUUGUAGCUACUCUGUGAUUGUGAUGCAAGAAAACAGCCAUAGACAACAGGUAAGCUAAUGAGUGUUCCAAUAAAACUUUAUUUAGAAAAAUAGGCAUCAGCCUUUUGUAGUUUGCUGAUCUCUUGCAUAGAGGAAAAAGACACAUUUGCAUUUUCUGCAGCCUACUAGUUUCAACAGGAAGAAAAGGGGCCCAGCAGAAUCCUGCAUACCAAGGAUUUUUCCUCACCAGUUUUUCACCAGAUUAAAAUACUCCAUCUUACCAGAAUUAGAGGGAGUAAAGGGAGAGAAAGAAACCUGAAAUAAUACUAAUGAGCUCUCCUUGUAAGAAGGGGGGCAAACGCUUUUCUCACAAGUCCCUUGACACUAGAAUUUACUCUGUUACUCAGGUAUACUGCCUUUCCAGUGGACUCAAAAGAACCUAUAAAACACAAAGUAUUACUUUGUACUGCAUUUUCCAAACUUGAGAGUCUAAGUGUUUUGGUGCUAAUUUUGGCGUAGUUUCUCUCAUUUUUUGGUUAGUGAUAGUAAAACCAUGUAAUGAGCUCCCAGGAAGACCCUUCUCUUCCGGCCACAUGUGUUGACAUGAGGACAUGCCUUUGGCCUAUUUUGGGCAGCUAAGAUUACUCUGUGGAUUGAUUCAUAUUUUUUGAGUGCCUACAAAAUAUGAGGCAUUUUGAUAAAUGCUGGGGAUACAAUAAUGAGCAAUAGUGAUCCAGUUCUUACCCUCACAAGAGCUUGUGCUGUGUAACAGAAAGGGCUCUAAAAAGAAAAAGUGAUUUCUAAUUUGAAACCUGAGGGACUAGCAGCACAUGCCAAAGGGGACAAAGUUCAGCAUGUUCCGGGAUUUGGGGAAAGCAUUGUUUAUCUGGGGAACAGAGUGUAAGGGGAAAAUGGAGAUAGAUAGCUGAGGCUGGAAAAGGAGGAGGGAGCCUAGGUUGCAAAACCUGUGUAAGCACUUGGGUUUUGUCAGAUCAGCAGGACGUGGUUGAGGGGCUUUAAAGCCAUAAGAUGAUGUGAAUGAUCUCUGUUUUUGAAUAUGUUCAGUCUAGGUUAGAAGAGGCAAAAAUUGAAGACCUACAUUUGUACUGUUCAACAAAGUAGCCAUGGGCCAAAGUGGCUGUUGAGCACUUGAAAGGAGAAUAUAUAAAAAACUGGAGGCCAAGAUACUUCCUUUUGAAGACAGAUGGCUCAUUCAUAGGAUAUAAAGAGAAACCUCAAGAUGUGGAUUUACCUUAUCCCCUCAACAACUUUUCAGUGGCAAGUACUGAGGGGAAAAAAGAAGGAAAUAAGGAAACCAACCUUUCUUUGAGCGUUACUAUGUAUCAAGCCCUUUCACAUAUGUUUUCUCAUUUUAUCUUCACAACAACACUGUGAGAAUGCCAGUUAAUGAAAACAGAACGACCAAAGCCAAACACAUUUAUAAUCAGAUGUCUCCAGUGGACUACUGUUAUAGAGAGAACAUUUCAUGUAGAUACUCCAGAGGAAAGGGAAGAAUGGACAGAAGCUAUCCAGGCUGUAGCAGACAGACUGCAGAGGCAAGAAGAGGAGAGAAUGAAUUGUAGUCCAACUUCACAAAUUGAUAAUAUAGGAGAGGAAGAGAUGGAUGCCUCUACAACCCAUCAUAAAAGAAAGACAAUGAAUGAUUUUGACUAUUUGAAACUACUAGGUAAAGGCACUUUUGGGAAAGUUAUUUUGGUUCGAGAGAAGGCAAGUGGAAAAUACUAUGCUAUGAAGAUUCUGAAGAAAGAAGUCAUUAUUGCAAAGGAUGAAGUGGCACACACUCUAACUGAAAGCAGAGUAUUAAAGAACACUAGACAUCCCUUUUUAACAUCCUUGAAAUAUUCCUUCCAGACAAAAGACCGUUUGUGUUUUGUGAUGGAAUAUGUUAAUGGGGGCGAGCUGUUUUUCCAUUUGUCGAGAGAGCGGGUGUUCUCUGAGGACCGCACACGUUUCUAUGGUGCAGAAAUUGUCUCUGCCUUGGACUAUCUACAUUCCGGAAAGAUUGUGUACCGUGAUCUCAAGUUGGAGAAUCUAAUGCUGGACAAAGAUGGCCACAUAAAAAUUACAGAUUUUGGACUUUGCAAAGAAGGGAUCACAGAUGCAGCCACCAUGAAGACAUUCUGUGGCACUCCAGAAUAUCUGGCACCAGAGGUGUUAGAAGAUAAUGACUAUGGCCGAGCAGUAGACUGGUGGGGCCUAGGGGUUGUCAUGUAUGAAAUGAUGUGUGGGAGGUUACCUUUCUACAACCAGGACCAUGAGAAACUUUUUGAAUUAAUAUUAAUGGAAGACAUUAAAUUUCCUCGAACACUCUCUUCAGAUGCAAAAUCAUUGCUUUCAGGGCUCUUGAUAAAGGAUCCAAAUAAACGCCUUGGUGGAGGACCAGAUGAUGCAAAAGAAAUUAUGAGACACAGUUUCUUCUCUGGAGUAAACUGGCAAGAUGUAUAUGAUAAAAAGCUUGUACCUCCUUUUAAACCUCAAGUAACAUCUGAGACAGAUACUAGAUAUUUUGAUGAAGAAUUUACAGCUCAGACUAUUACAAUAACACCACCUGAAAAAUAUGAUGAGGAUGGUAUGGACUGCAUGGACAAUGAGAGGCGGCCGCAUUUCCCUCAAUUUUCCUACUCUGCAAGUGGACGAGAAUAAGUCUCUUUCAUUCUGCUACUUCACUGUCAUCUUCAAUUUAUUACUGAAAAUGAUUCCUGGACAUCACCAGUCCUAGCUCUUACACAUAGCAGGGGCACCUUCCGACAUCCCAGACCAGCCAAGGGUCCUCACCCCUCGCCACCUUUCACCCUCAUGAAAACACACAUACACGCAAAUACACUCCAGUUUUUGUUUUUGCAUGAAAUUGUAUCUCAGUCUAAGGUCUCAUGCUGUUGCUGCUACUGUCUUACUAUUAUAGCAACUUUAAGAAGUAAUUUUCCAACCUUUGGAAGUCAUGAGCCCACCAUUGUUCAUUUGUGCACCAAUUAUCAUCUUUUGAUCUUUUAGUUUUUCCCUCAGUGAAGGCUAAAUGAGAUACACUGAUUCUAGGUACAUUUUUUAACUUUCUAGAAGAGAAAAACUAACUAGACUAAGAAGAUUUAGUUUAUAAAUUCAGAACAAGCAAUUGUGGAAGGGUGGUGGCGUGCAUAUGUAAAGCACAUCAGAUCCGUGCGUGAAGUAGGCAUAUAUCACUAAGCUGUGGCUGGAAUUGAUUAGGAAGCAUUUGGUAGAAGGACUGAACAACUGUUGGGAUAUAUAUAUAUAUAUAUAAUUUUUUUUUUUUAAAUUCCUGGUGGAUACUGUAGAAGAAGCCCAUAUCACAUGUGGAUGUCGAGACUUCACGGGCAAUCAUGAGCAAGUGAACACUGUUCUACCAAGAACUGAAGGCAUAUGCACAGUCAAGGUCACUUAAAGGGUCUUAUGAAACAAUUUGAGCCAGAGAGCAUCUUUCCCCUGUGCUUGGAAACCUUUUUUCCUUCUUGACAUUUAUCACCUCUGAUGGCUGAAGAAUGUAGACAGGUAUAAUGAUACUGCUUUUCACCAAAAUUUCUACACCAAGGUAAACAGGUGUUUGCCUUAUUUAAUUUUUUACUUUCAGUUCUACGUGAAUUAGCUUUUUCUCAGAUGUUGAAACUUUGAAUGUCCUUUUAUGAUUUUGUUUAUAUUGCAGUAGUAUUUAUUUUUUAGUGAUGAGAAUUGUAUGUCAUGUUAGCAAACGCAGCUCCAACUUAUAUAAAAUAGACUUACUGCAGUUACUUUUGACCCAUGUGCAAGGAUUGUACACGCUGAUGAGAAUCAUGCACUUUUUCUCCUCUGUUAAAAAAAAUGAUAAGGCUCUGAAAUGGAAUAUAUUGGUUAGAAUUUGGCUUUGGGAGAAGAGAUGCUGCCAUUUAACCCCUUGGUACUGAAAAUGAGAAAAUCCCCAACUAUGCAUGCCAAGGGGUUAAUGAAACAAAUAGCUGUUGACGUUUGCUCAUUUAAGAAUUUGAAACGUUAUGAUGACCUGGCAACAAAAAGUAAUGAAGAAAAUUGAGACCUGAGUGAAGAUAAGAAAUGAUCUUUACGUGGCAAAAUGAACACAUCUUGAGUAUUUAGGAAAUGGGCAGUGAAGGCUAAGAACCUGGUGUGUUUCUUGGGAUCAUGGUACAUUUAUCACUGAAUUAAGCCAUCAGGGAAAAAACAACAAAAAAAGAGAACACCUCCAGCUUUUCUUUUUCUGUAUAUACUCAUGUCCCCCAGAUUCCAACAUUUCUCACUGAAAGGGGGCAUGUAUGCAAACCUCAUCUUUCUCCUUCAUUAAUGAUGAUCUUCAGAUUAAACCCUUUGGUGCUAGGAGCUGACAAUUUCCAAAGCAGCCUGUGAAGUCCUAGGGGCUGGGGGCCACUCUUGCGGCAAGCAGAAGGCCAUCCUACUCCGCGGAGUGAUCAUGGAAAUGUAUUUUAGUUAAACUCUGACAGCUCCCAAACGGAAGACUACAGCAUGACGUAGUAUUAUGAUUGCAUUGUAUGAAAGAGCAAGUGACUUUCUAAGUAGGAUGAAUCAUAUUCAUAUGCAGAUGUCUUAGCCUCUUGACGCUGGAAGUGUGGAUUUAUAGCUAUGAAACCACUGCUGGCAGUGGGUGGGCCACUGGGACUGACGGGGGUUAAAGGGCAUUUUACUAAGGCAGCUAAGACAUAUUCAGACAUCAACGUUAUCCUUCUUUUUCAUAUUUCUACCUGAGUGAAGUUCAUCCUUAGUAUUGAGUAGGAAGUUACAGUAAAUGGUAGUUCAUUCUUACUUACACACAUAGCUAAUCUUUUUUUUUUCACUUGGAAUUAUGUUGAAUGUUUCAUUUUGACAAAAAAGUAGACUAGAAGGUAUGUUCUUUAAGUUGUCUUGCAUCCAUUAUAUAAGAAAGAAACAGGUGAGAGGAAGAGCAGAAAGCUGAGACUGGCUGAUGUUCAGAGCACUUACUCCUCUAGAGGGAAAGCAUGACACCGAACACUAAGCACACAGCUUUUUGUUGUUUUGGUUUUUUCUCCCGCAAAUCUUAAAGUGAUUCCCAUGACCUUGGCCAAGGACACUUCUUAAAGAUUAAUGACUGGCACUGACAUUGCCCCAGGCGGGCCACUCCUCACACUGGCUCUCAGUUCCCAGCCAUGCCUGGGGCUCAGUCACUUCUAUUCCACCCUCUGAGACUCCAUUGGUGUCACACAAGGUGUCUUCUUGGCUUUGAUUUUGAGAAUCCCCUAUUUUCACUUCCAGAUCUGUCAGCUGCCAUGGAGGAAUAAUAGAAAACCAGAAAUGCGUGUAGAGGGAGAUUUCUAAAACUUCCCUUGUGUCGCCCAUAGUUGUAGUUUUGGGUUCUGGCAGGUGGAACACCCUGAAACCUGGAAUCAUUCUAUGAGAAUACAGUUCAGACUUUGCAGACUCCAGCCCAUACUAACUGUCAUGAAGCUUGACUUCUUGUCAUAAUGCAGCCAUCUUGGAGGAAAUUGGCCAUUUCUGCUUAGAUGGUUGGCAGGGUCGCGCUCAGCUUUGCUUUCUACACUAAUUACAUAGCAUUAUUCAAGUAUUGUUUUCCAUUUCCCAUCCCUGAUUUCCAGCUUCUUAAAGCUGACUGUUCUUGCAGGGGCCACUUGCUUCUCCUAGAGUACAAAAGUAAGGGCCUUCCUUACUAACUGCAGGGUCUCUCUAUUACACCUCAACAUACACACUUUGCUGCUACUGUUUGUACUGUCUACAGUAGAAUUUCCUUAUCUUGCUCCUGGUAGUGCAUUACAGGCAAGCAUGAAAUGUAAAGUAUUUAUUUAAAUAAAAAGAAAACCUCUAAAUUGGUAAUUGAAUUACCUCCCUGUAGCUUUAUAGUUUGUGACAUUUCUUGACCUUGCUAGUUCUUUCAUUAGAUCUGCGCAAGAUCUAGUCAUCUGGUUAAGGAUUUUAAGCAGAUGCAACUAUAAACCCAAGAAACUGUAUUACUAUUACUGUUGGUCAUACUAAACCUGUCUAUUUCCUGAAGUAUAUGACCCACAAGGAUGUGGAAUAACUAGGAGAAACUGUUUUUGUACACUGUACAUCCUUAGUAUUUUUACACGUAUAUGAUAGGGAUGAACAUGAUUUUCCUUCGUACAGACAGCUUAAAUAAAGCACUAUGUCAAUCUGCUACUUCUCUGUUUAUUGUUGUUGGAUGUGGUUCUAUAAUCCCCCCAAAUUAAAUCUUCUUUAAUGAAAACAUGAUUUUUAAUAGCCCCAGCUGGUAUUAACCUACCUUGUAUAAAAUGUGACAGGAAAAUAUAGAAAUAAUUCCUUGUAGCUCACACACACACACAUAGGGGAUCAUUUUUACUUCAGUGAAAUGGCAGUAGUGCGGUUGUGCAAACUUUGAUGAACGGCUGCUUCUGAGGGGAAACGCUGACCUCUCAGCACUGGAUUUAGGAUGGAUGUACUGUGAAGCCAGGGAUGAAGGAGGUCUCAGACCCUGGGGACAUUCAGACCCGAAUCAUCUAUACAACACACGGUUUGGACCCAGAAUCUGAAGGAAUGUAGCUUUUCAUUAACGUCUUCCUGAUAAUGUACUGCUCUGCAUAUUUCCUUUCUUAGAGUGUAUUUCUAACAACAUGUCAUGGCAAAUUAACAAACUUAGACGUGGGUGAUGUAGAUGGGUAGGAUGGCUGGACUGCAGUCUGACUUCACGUUGAAUCAUUCUGGAUGGGGCCUUUUUCUGAUUUUACCUCAUAAAGCUACUAUUGUAGAAACUUGGCUUUGCUCCUGUGACGAAGCCAGACAGAGGAAUGGCUUUUGGGACCAGAGUGAGUCAAGCAUGUAUGUGUAUGUCACACGGCCAAAUUUGAGGGCAUUCUCACAUGUGCUCUUCUCUCAAAACCACUGGGGUUGACAGAUCCAGGAGGCUAAAAAAAAGUGACCUCUAUAAUUCUUUAAAGGUGCUAUUUUUAGAAUAUUGUAUAAUUUAUUCACAGUAUAUCUAAAACAGAAUUAAGGACAAUUAAAAUAUCUUAUGUGACAGCCUUUAUGUCUAGCACAUUUGAUGAAAUAAAAAACUUCUGAAUCUGAAUAGAAGUUCUACUGUUUCAGGCUUGAACCUUUUACAUGCUCAAGAGAUUCAAAUGGUCUCUGUGUGUAGAUCAUGCCACCGCCUCCAAAGCCUAAUCCACAUCACUUCUGAGAGGCAAGGCUGAGCAUAUGGUGACAUCAGCUCUGUGUUGAGAUGGUGAUGAGGAUGAUGGCUCGCUGGCCAGGCAGGGCAGCCGAAGGUCAGGGACCUGUCCUAACUAACUGCAGCCUUGCCUUUAGUGUUUGUCAUUCUCAGAUACAACACGGUAUGUCCAGUGUCCGUUUUUAUUACUUUAAAGCAUUUGAGGGCUUAAUUGUGUAUAGUAGAAAUACUAUUUUAGACAAAUAAUUAUCUGUGUACAGAUAUUUGAUAUACUCUAAGUAAAUUUUCUAAUUUCACUAAGUACGUUUUUAGGCUCCUCUCAAAUACUGCGUAUUGAAGAAAAAAAUCUGACACCACCGAGCCAAAGAUGCUUUUUUGUCUGUUUUCGUUGUUUAACAGAAUGGAAAGAGUAAUGCAUAGUGCUUCCUGGUGUCUCCUGAUUGAUUGAUUGUGCACAAAGUAGGACGAUAAAUAAAUAAAAUGGAGUCUGAUGGGACAUUGAUUAAAGGUGAAGGAUGAUUGAUAUAUAGAUCAUGAAAAGAAAAAUGAAUGGCAGGAAAAAAAGUUUGGUCCUUAAUAUACUUUGGCCUAGUUAAAAUAUGUGCCUUUUUGGUGUGUUUUGUUCAUCACUACAAGAUAAAAAGGAAACAUUACAACUCAAGUCUUUAAAAAGUUCAUUUAUUGAAAAUCAUAUGUAUAACCUAGCAUACGAAUGAGCAGAUUUAAACACAUAACUUCAAGCCAUUUCUGAAAACAUACACCAGGAGCUCUGCUCAGCUAGAGUCAGACUCCAGCUCCAGCCCGACUGCGUGCGGGGACAGCGCCCGCGUUGAUGAGGACCAGCCCCACUGCAGGCUGAGGCGGUGUCACCCUGGGAAGGUCGUGGUGCGUUGUGGCAUAUUAAGUCUAAACCAGAUGAAUGUAAAUAUCUCUUUGUAAAUCAUUUAUUUCACUCUGUUCCAUCCAGGUCAGCAAUCAGAUUGUGGCAUGCUGGGUAACUGGAAAAAAUAAUAAAAAGUAAGUUUCAAUA